ACACUUCCCCGCCCUCGCCCCAAAGGAGCAGCAGCUCCUUCUUGCCUCUCCAUUGCCGCCGCCGCACCGGCGGAGCUCCUCUCUCGCGCGUCUCUCCUCCGAUGGAGCUCGGGCGCCGCCGACGCCGCCGCUGCCCCGAACCCUGAGCGGGGCCGCCCCGGUCGGAGGAACGCGCCGCCCAGUCCGAGGGCGCAGAGCGCCAGGAGCACGCGGAGGGCUGGGGCGCGGGCUCCGGGAACGAGAAAGUGCAGCUCUCUCGGGUCACUGGGCCGGCGGCGGGGGGACUAUGGCUCUGAAGGACACGGGCAGCGGCGGCAGCACCAUCCUGCCCAUUAGCGAGAUGGUUUCCUCGUCCAGCUCGCCCGGCGCGUCGGCCGCCGCCGCCCCGGGGCCCUGCGCACCCUCGCCCUUCCCUGAAGUAGUGGAGCUGAACGUAGGCGGCCAGGUUUAUGUGACCAAGCACUCGACGCUGCUCAGCGUCCCGGACAGUACUUUGGCCAGCAUGUUCUCGCCCUCUAGUCCCCGUGGCGGCGCCCGGCGCCGGGGCGAGCUGCCCAGGGACAGCCGGGCGCGCUUCUUCAUCGACCGGGACGGCUUCCUUUUCAGGUACGUGCUGGAUUAUCUGCGGGACAAGCAACUCGCGCUGCCGGAGCACUUCCCCGAGAAGGAGCGGCUGCUGCGCGAGGCCGAGUAUUUCCAGCUCACCGACUUGGUCAAGCUGCUGUCGCCCAAGGUCACCAAGCAGAACUCUCUCAACGACGAGGGCUGCCAGAGCGACCUGGAGGACAACGUCUCGCAGGGUAGCAGCGACGCGCUGCUGCUGCGCGGGGCGGCGGCCGCCGUGCCCUCGGGCCCGGGAGCGCACGGUGGUGGCGGCGGCGGCGGCGCGCAGGACAAGCGCUCGGGCUUCCUCACGCUGGGCUACCGGGGCUCCUACACCACCGUGCGCGACAACCAGGCCGACGCCAAAUUCCGGCGUGUGGCGCGCAUCAUGGUGUGCGGGCGCAUCGCGCUGGCCAAGGAGGUCUUCGGGGACACGCUCAACGAGAGCCGCGACCCCGACCGGCAGCCGGAGAAGUACACGUCCCGCUUCUACCUCAAGUUCACCUACUUGGAGCAGGCCUUUGAUCGCCUGUCCGAGGCCGGCUUCCACAUGGUGGCGUGUAACUCCUCGGGCACCGCCGCCUUCGUCAACCAGUACCGCGACGACAAGAUCUGGAGCAGCUACACCGAGUACAUUUUCUUCCGUUUGAAUAUAUGGCUAUUUAUGAUUGCUUGCCAGAUCAAGCAUGAAUCAAGAUGCAGAACCAGGGCCAGAUGCUUGGCAGCAGGACCACCUCAGAAAAUAGUAUCACCUAAACAAGAACAUGAAGAUAGGAAACAUGACAAAGUCACUGAUAAAGGAAGUGAAAGUGGGACUUCCUGUAAUGAGCUCUCCACUUCCAGUUGUGACAGCCAUUCAGAGGCAAGCACUCCCCAGGACAACCCAUCCAGUGCCCAGCAGGCAACAGCUCACCAACCUAACACUUUAACAUUGGAUCGCCCCUCUAAAAAAGCACCUGUACAAUGGAUACCCCCACCAGACAAACGCAGAAACAGUGAACUCUUUCAGACCCUCAUCAGCAAGUCCCGGGAAACAAAUCUGUCCAAAAAGAAAGUCUGUGAGAAGCUAAGUGUGGAAGAAGAAAUGAAAAAGUGUAUUCAGGAUUUUAAAAAAAUCCACAUUCCAGAUUAUUUUCCAGAGCGCAAACGCCAAUGGCAAUCUGAACUGUUGCAGAAGUAUGGGUUAUAGUAAUUGUCACAUUCCUGCAGUAUUUUGAUGACAUUCAAUGUUUACUACAGUGUCACCACCUGACUGAUGUCCUAACAAUGGUCAGUGUGAUUCUUGCUGCUCUUCCUUGUUGUGAACAGUGGAUGUGGGACAGUAUUUUCUUUUAUGUUUUAGUUGUUGUUCUUUUUAGAAACAUGAUUAAAAAGGAAAAAAUAUUAAAUCAAUAAGUGUUAAAUCAAAAUGGAAUAUCUGAUUCAAACCAUUUUACAAGAAUGAAAGUAAAAUGUGCAUGAUCAAGCUUAGUAUCUUGGUUUUUGAACUCUGGUCAACUGGAUAUGUUUGUCAUUUUGUAACUUACCAAAAACAAACCAUCAUAUCAUACCAACUAAAAUGAUAUAUGGAUGAAGCAACAUCAAGUAAAAUUUUAGACGAUGGCUAUAGGACCCAAAUCUAAAGCUGUCUAAAUGUUAAUUCAAUGAAACAAGUAUUAUUUUUGCAUGAAUACAAUGUUACAAAUAAAUCACAAGAAAUAGGGAAGAUCUGUUUGUUGCUUGGAAAGAAAAAAAUUACAAAAAAAAGCAAAAAAAAAUGUUUUAGACAAAGCCUAUAAAUGUAAGCUGUCUAGGAGAUUGAAUUUUCUUUGUUCUGGAUCUGUGACUUUUUUGUGUAUGUGUAUGGUGUUUAUGUAUAUUAAGAUGGUGUAAAUAUGCCUUAUACUGUUAUUUAUGGCAUCAACAUUCAUUUACUAAUGCUAGUCAUGAUUAUUACUGUGAAAUGAGUCUUACAUCGGGCUGUGAAAAUUGGUAUAAUGAUGCUUUGAAAGAUCCUAUUAUCAUGUUAAUCAAAAUAAUAGAGGGAAAUGGUAAAGAGCUUUAUGUAUUUAUUAAAAAAAGAAAAAUGUAUUAGAA